AUUUUUAAGGAUGGAAAAAUAGAAGCAGAAGAUUUCACAAGCAGGUUAUACCGAGAACUUAAUUCUUCACCUCAACCUUACCUUGUGCCUUUCCUGAAGAGGAGCUUACCCGCCUUGAGACAGCUGACCCCCGACUCCGCGGCCUUCAUCCAGCAGAGCCAGCAGCAGCCGCCACCGCCCACCUCGCAGGCCACCACUGCGCUCACGGCCGUGGUGCUGAGUAGCUCGGUCCAGCGCACGGCCGGGAAGACGGCGGCCACCGUGACCAGUGCCCUCCAGCCCCCUGUGCUCAGCCUCACGCAGCCCACGCAGGUCGGCGUCGGCAAGCAGGGGCAACCCACACCGCUGGUCAUCCAGCAGCCUCCGAAGCCAGGAGCCCUGAUCCGGCCCCCGCAGGUGACGUUGACGCAGACACCCAUGGUCGCCCUGCGGCAGCCUCACAACCGGAUCAUGCUCACCACGCCUCAGCAGAUCCAGCUGAACCCACUGCAGCCAGUCCCUGUGGUGAAACCCGCCGUGUUACCUGGAACCAAAGCCCUUUCUGCUGUCUCGGCACAAGCAGCUGCUGCACAGAAAAAUAAACUCAAGGAGCCUGGGGGAGGUUCGUUUCGGGACGAUGAUGACAUUAAUGAUGUUGCAUCGAUGGCUGGAGUAAACUUGUCAGAAGAAAGUGCAAGAAUAUUAGCCACGAACUCUGAAUUGGUGGGCACGCUAACGCGGUCCUGUAAAGAUGAAACCUUCCUCCUCCAAGCGCCUUUGCAGAGAAGAAUAUUAGAAAUAGGUAAAAAACAUGGUAUAACGGAAUUACAUCCAGAUGUAGUAAGUUAUGUAUCACAUGCCACGCAACAAAGGCUACAGAAUCUUGUAGAGAAAAUAUCAGAAACAGCUCAGCAGAAGAACUUUUCUUACAAGGAUGACGACAGAUAUGAGCAGGCGAGUGACGUCCGGGCACAGCUCAAGUUUUUUGAACAGCUUGAUCAAAUCGAAAAGCAGAGGAAGGAUGAGCAGGAGCGGGAGAUCCUGAUGAGGGCAGCAAAGUCUCGGUCAAGACAAGAAGAUCCAGAACAGUUAAGGCUGAAACAGAAGGCAAAGGAGAUGCAGCAACAGGAACUGGCACAAAUGAGACAGCGGGACGCCAACCUCACAGCACUAGCAGCGAUCGGGCCCAGGAAAAAGAGGAAAGUGGACUGUCCGGGGCCGGGCUCAGGAGCAGAGGGGUCGGGCCCCGGCUCAGUGGUCCCAGGCAGCUCGGGUGUCGGAACCCCCAGACAGUUCACGCGACAAAGAAUCACGCGGGUCAACCUCAGGGACCUCAUAUUUUGUUUAGAAAAUGAACGUGAGACAAGCCAUUCACUGCUGCUCUACAAAGCAUUCCUUAAGUGACACAGGAGGACGCCUGGGGACUUUUUAUAUAUUUGCAGAUUACGCCUUUUUGUAACGAGCAAAUGGGAUAUUGUUUAAAAAACAGCCACCUCUUUACAAUGGAACAGUUUUAUAUUCCUGUUUCUAAAUCAGCUCUUCAGUGUGAAAGAAAACACGUUUCUGUAACAGAGAGAACACAAAGGCCUGUGGAUACUCUUAAAGGACAAUUAAAUCUUAACUCAUCUUGAUUGAGUGGCCUUCCUGCCAAACAAGCCAUAUAUAAAGACUGAUGGAAUCGUUAGCAAAUAAUUAGCUGCCCUCUGUCAACUCAUAGCAGUUUCUGCAUUAUUUGUGCAUUUUGGUUUAGUUCUACCUAACUUACUAUGUAGGUGUAUGUCUACAGCCGAUGACCUCAUUUCGUUUAUUUUAUUUUUGUAAUAGUCAGUUGGCAAAGCAAACUGAUUUUUUAGACUAUUUAUCUUCCUUCCCUUCCCCUCCCACCCCGCUCUCCUCUCUGCCCCCUGCCCUCCCCUCCCCUCCCUUCCCCUCCACUCCGCUGAGAAUCCUGGAGGAAUACACAAUUCAUCGUUGCACCCCCACCUCAGAGUGUAAUCGCAUUUCUGCUUGGUAGAGGCCGAGCCCAGCAAAGGUGGCUCCUUCUGAAUGUGUGGUCAGCAUCUGUACAAAUGCAUUUUAUUUGCUAUAGUUUGUAAAGCUGUAAAGUUAAAAGAGAUGAAAACCUUUUCAGCAUAAAUAUAUUUUACUUGCACUGUGUUUUUUAGCUAAAAGUGAAAACCUAGAUUAAAUAAAAUCAAAGUUGAGAAGAAUCAUCAAAAGACUGUUUCUCGGUGUGAAUCAAGUGUUGAAAAAUGGUUGGUGUAUUUUGUCAGUAAUUGUACAUAACUUUUGGCACAUGACAUAGAAAUGGCUAUGUAAACUAUAAUUAUUUUGCUAAGAGACUGUAUGCAAGCCUUGGGCCGACUUUACAGACGUCCAGAGCAAAGCCCCUUCUUUGUACCUAUUUUUUUAUUACAAAUAUACUAAUUGGUUCUUUCUAUUUUCAGAGGUUAUUGUAUGAAAUUGUCUAUUGAUAGUACUUUUAUGACUGUAAAUACUCUGGCUUUCUCCGUGUGAAUUCUCACAUUAGACUUUAAUUCGAGCGCGUGUGAACUGAACGCUGAUCAGUAUUUUUUAUCAACACCUGAGAACUGUUACACCUUUUAUUUUGUCUUUUAGGAAAUCCCUGUCUUUCCAUUUUUUCAUGUAAAUUUUGCACAGUUACUUGUUCAUAUGUAAAUAUUUUACUUUCAGAAAUGAAGUUUUUAAUUGCUAUUGUUUUAUAUAGGAUUGAAAGAAAAUUAACUCCUUUAUUAAAAACAAAUUUAUCUGUA